ACUGCGCUCUGACCCAGACCCGGCUGACCCACCUACCCGCGAUCCUGCCCAUGGCUGACGGGCUCUUUCGGCGCAGACCCUGGGGUCUCGAGCAGAUUCGCCCGGACCCCGAGUCCGAAGGCCUGUUUGACAAGCCUCCCCCGGAAGACCCUCCCGCUGCCCGCGGGCCCAGGUCGGCGUCGGCCGCGGGCAAGAAGGCUGGUCGGCGCGCGGGCGGGAGGGCGCAGGGGGGCCGCGCCGGGCAGCCCCCGAAGGCCGCAUCGCGCCCCCCGCCCAAGAAGGAGGCGCCUCCACUGGACGAGGGCUGCUAUCUCGACCAUUUUCCGCACCUCUCCAUCUUCAUCUACGCAGCCAUCGCCUUCUCCAUCACCUCCUGCAUCUUUACCUAUAUCCAUUUACAGCUUGCCUGAGUGGCCAGCGCGGGACGGGGUGGGCGCAGGACCGAGCGGGGAGGGAAAGGGAAAACGGGGCUCGGCAUUUUGUGUUUUAGAACAGCGCUGCACCCCCUUCAUGUAGCUUUCGAUGCUUGUUUCUUUCCGUCUUUGUUGUCACUAUCUUUGUCUAUCAGUACGAAAGUACAAAGUAGCUGCCGGCAAUGAAAUAGGGGUGCUGUUUGCACCUGCAGGUUAGGGGUGGAGGCGUUUAGAAUUUUGGGGUGUGAUUGAGCCCCGUUUAUAAUUAGAAUGCCCCUGGACCCCUACCACUCUGUGACGUGGGGGCACGCGCAGGGAUCCCAUCAUUUUGUGUUUGGGGAGCUCAGAGUGCGCCCAAUCUUGGAAUCUUUAAGGGAUGAGCCAGACCCAGACCCGCGGCCUUCUAGAGAGGGUCCGGCAGGGAGGGUCGGCGCCCUGGCCCGGGGUGGGCCGGAGCCCUGUGAUGCUGCAUCGCCCCCAGGAGGAGCCAGCUGUGCCCCAGAGUUGGCGCGGCCGAGAGAGGACAAGAGCGCGCAGCAGGCGAAGCUGGAGGGCGGGACUCGACUUUGUUGUCGCUGCCCGGAGGAGUCGAGACUGGUACCCGGAGGAGCUGUCUCACCAGGAGACCACGUCCUGGAAGUGUCCGGGACUCGCGGGACCUGUGGCUGCAGACCCCGCCGGCACGCAGGCCCAGAGCUGGCGCACUCCUGAGGAUGAGACUCUGGGGGCCCUAGCCGGGGUCCACGGGAGGGCUGUCCUUGGGGACUCUAGGAUGGCUUCGUUCUGGCCCGGCUCACUUCUGGAGCUGUGAGACCCAAGACAAAAGGGGCUGAGGGAUUUCUCAUUGACAAGAGUUCGUGCGGGAAAACCACCUGAUCCCUAGGGAUUUGUCAUCUUAAGACUCAAAAGGCUUAAUACCAGGAACCACCUUGGCAAGAUAUUUACCCACCGGCCAUCUCUGUUUACUCAUGAAUGUUAAAUGUUAAAACGCAGCGCUCUAACCCUGCAUAUUAUUUACUUGCAAAUGUCUGUAAUCUGUAAUUGUGAUGCCUCUGAUGGAAUAAAUUAUCUUUUUCAGUCUCCUCUA